GGGAACCACUCAGACCGCAGUGGACGUUCCUAAACUUCUGUGGACUCACGGCAGAUUCUCUGCAAGAGAUUUCCUCAAGGGCUGGAUUCCACAAGCCCUUCUGUCCUGCUGCGGGCCUCAGGCAGUGUUCCCGCCAAGCUUUCCCUAAAGACACAAACAGGCAGGCCCUUCCCACACGGGCCUCAGGGAGCCUUCUGCUGGGCAGAGCGUCCCUGCCAGGGGAAGCCAGGCUCGUUAAGUGGGAAGCCUGUGGGGCCUGCGGAAGACAGCGGCCCUGAGGCUGUCUCCACCGCCAGUUGGUGCCACCAAGCCUUCGGGAGGGAGUGGCCAUCCCCACUGGGGUUGGGAAAUGGAGAGAGAGGUUACAGUGGGUGGCUGCAGCCCUGUAAGAACCACGGAGUUCCUUCAGUGGCAAAGACCAGAGCCCCAGGGCUGAGCCGAGCUGCCGUAGCCAUGGGACCUGCUCUCCUGGCCCUCUCCUUCCUGUGGACCAUGGCCUUGACUGAAGACACCUGUCCAGAGGUGAAGAUGGUGGGCCUGGAGGGCUCUGACAAGCUCACCAUUCUCCGAGGCUGUCCGGGGCUGCCUGGGGCCCCUGGGCCCAAGGGAGAGGCAGGCACCAAUGGAAAGAGAGGAGAACGUGGCCCCCCUGGACCUCCUGGGAAGGCAGGACCACCUGGGCCCAACGGAGCACCUGGGGAGCCCCAGCCGUGCCUGACAGGCCCGCGUACCUGCAAGGACCUGCUAGACCGAGGGCACUUCCUGAGCGGCUGGCACACCAUCUACCUGCCCGACUGCCGGCCCCUGACUGUGCUCUGUGACAUGGACACGGACGGAGGGGGCUGGACCGUUUUCCAGCGGAGGGUGGAUGGCUCUGUGGACUUCUACCGGGACUGGGCCACGUACAAGCAGGGCUUCGGCAGUCGGCUGGGGGAGUUCUGGCUGGGGAAUGACAACAUCCACGCCCUGACCGCCCAGGGAACCAGCGAGCUCCGUGUAGACCUGGUGGACUUUGAGGACAACUACCAGUUUGCUAAGUACAGAUCAUUCAAGGUGGCCGACGAGGCGGAGAAGUACAAUCUGGUCCUGGGGGCCUUCGUGGAGGGCAGUGCGGGAGAUUCCCUGACGUUCCACAACAACCAGUCCUUCUCCACCAAAGACCAGGACAAUGAUCUUAACACCGGAAAUUGUGCUGUGAUGUUUCAGGGAGCUUGGUGGUACAAAAACUGCCAUGUGUCAAACCUGAAUGGUCGCUACCUCAGGGGGACUCAUGGCAGCUUUGCAAAUGGCAUCAACUGGAAGUCGGGGAAAGGAUACAAUUAUAGCUACAAGGUGUCAGAGAUGAAGGUGCGACCUGCCUAGCCCAGGCCGGCCUCAGGGUCAGGACGCCUCCACACAUAGUUGGUUGGGGGGUAGGGUUGGGAGCUUGGCCCUACGGUUUGUAAAAGAAACACAUGUCGUGAUUCUAAA